GUAGACGCUGCUGGGCAGAGGUUUAAGGAAGGAGUCCGGGCAGAUGCCUAGGUUUAAAACCCGUGAGGGUGGAGCAAAGCCAUUCUCUUCUCCUGGUAGAAUCUUAGGGCCUGAGUCAUGGAAGGGUACAAUCUUUUGAUCUCAAAAAUUUUAAAACUGGAAGAACAGGAAGUGUCCACCCCCUGGGACUGGUCCCAUUUUUUUGGAGCUGGGCUGCUUCUGGCCCACGAAGGUGAAGGGGCCUGCCUGGUGACGUGGUGGAUGGUAAGCCUGAAGAAGCAGGGAGCCCAGAGGUUUUGGGGUCAGAGGAGCACCAGCCUAUGGCCCUGGACCCCUGGGGUAUUCAGCGAGUUCCUGGAGGACGGUGGGAUGGGGCUGUGGUUCCAGCAAGAAAAAACCGGGAAGAUCCUGACGGAGUUCCUCCAGUUCUAUGAAGACCAGUAUGGCGUGGCUCUCUUCAACAGCAUGCGCCAUGAGAUUGAGGGCACGGGGCUGCCGCAGGCCCAGCUGCUCUGGCGCAAGGUGCCACUGGACGAGCGCAUCGUCUUCUCGGGGAACCUCUUCCAGCACCAGGAGGACAGCAAGAAGUGGAGAAACCGCUUCAGCCUCGUGCCCCACAACUACGGGCUGGUGCUCUACGAAAACAAAGCGGCCUAUGAGCGGCAGGUCCCACCACGAGCCGUCAUCAACAGUGCAGGCUACAAAAUCCUCACGUCCGUGGACCAAUACCUGGAGCUCAUUGGCAACUCCUUACCAGGGACCACGGCAAAGUCGGGCAGUGCCCCCAUCCUCAAGUGCCCCACACAGUUCCCGCUCAUCCUCUGGCAUCCUUAUGCGCGUCACUACUACUUCUGCAUGAUGACAGAAGCCGAGCAGGACAAGUGGCAGGCUGUGCUGCAGGACUGCAUCCGGCACUGCAACAAUGGAAUCCCUGAGGACUCCAAGGUAGAGGGCCCUGCGUUCACAGAUGCCAUCCGCAUGUACCGACAGUCCAAGGAGCUGUACGGCACCUGGGAGAUGCUGUGUGGGAACGAGGUGCAGAUCCUGAGCAACCUGGUGAUGGAGGAGCUGGGCCCUGAGCUGAAGGCAGAGCUCGGCCCGCGGCUGAAGGGGAAACCGCAGGAGCGGCAGCGGCAGUGGAUCCAGAUCUCGGACGCCGUGUACCACAUGGUGUACGAGCAGGCCAAGGCGCGCUUCGAGGAGGUGCUGUCCAAGGUGCAGCAGGUGCAGCCGGCCAUGCAGGCCGUCAUCCGAACUGACAUGGACCAAAUUAUCACCUCCAAGGAGCACCUUGCCAGCAAGAUCCGAGCCUUCAUCCUCCCCAAGGCAGAGGUGUGCGUGCGGAACCAUGUCCAGCCCUACAUCCCAUCCAUCCUGGAGGCCCUGAUGGUCCCCACCAGCCAGGGCUUCACUGAGGUGCGAGAUGUCUUCUUCAAGGAGGUCACGGACAUGAACCUGAACGUCAUCAACGAGGGCGGCAUUGACAAGCUGGGCGAGUACAUGGAGAAGCUGUCCCGGCUGGCGUACCACCCCCUGAAGAUGCAGAGCUGCUAUGAGAAGAUGGAGUCGCUGCGACUGGACGGGCUGCAGCAGCGAUUUGAUGUGUCCAGCACGUCCGUGUUCAAGCAGCGAGCCCAGAUCCACAUGCGGGAGCAAAUGGACAAUGCCGUGUAUACGUUCGAGACCCUCCUGCACCAGGAGCUGGGGAAGGGGCCCACCAAGGAGGAGCUGUGCAAGUCCAUCCAGCGGGUCCUGGAGCGGGUGCUGAAGAAAUACGACUACGACAGCAGCUCUGUGCGGAAGAGGUUCUUCCGGGAGGCGCUGCUGCAGAUCAGCAUCCCGUUCCUGCUCAAGAAGCUGGCCCCUACCUGCAAGUCGGAGCUGCCCCGGUUCCAGGAGCUGAUCUUCGAGGACUUUGCCAGGUUCAUCCUGGUGGAAAACACGUACGAGGAGGUGGUGCUGCAGACCGUCAUGAAGGACAUCCUGCAGGCUGUGAAGGAGGCCGCGGUGCAGAGGAAGCACAACCUCUACCGGGACAGCAUGGUCAUGCACAACAGCGACCCCAACCUGCACCUGCUGGCCGAGGGCGCCCCCAUCGACUGGGGCGAGGAGUACAGCAACAGCGGCGGGGGCGGCAGCCCCAGCCCCAGCACCCCGGAGUCAGCCACCCUCUCGGAAAAGCGACGGCGCGCCAAGCAGGUGGUCUCUGUGGUCCAGGAUGAGGAGGUGGGGCUGCCCUUUGAGGCUAGCCCUGAGUCACCACCACCUGCGUCCCCGGACGGUGUCACUGAGAUCCGAGGCCUGCUGGCCCAAGGUCUGCGGCCUGAGAGCCCCCCACCAGCCGGCCCCCUGCUCAACGGGGCCCCCGCUGGGGAGAGUCCCCAGCCUAAGGCCGCCCCCGAGGCCUCCUCGCCGCCUGCCUCACCCCUCCAGCAUCUCCUGCCUGGAAAGGCUGUGGACCUUGGGCCCCCCAAGCCCAGCGACCAGGAGACUGGAGAGCAGGUGUCCAGCCCCAGCAGCCACCCCGCCCUCCACACCACCACCGAGGACAGUGCAGGGGUGCAGACUGAGUUCUAGGCCAGUGGGUCCCUGACUGCUGCACAUGGCACAGGCCGUUCCCUUCCGGACCCAGGCAGGCUCAGCUCUGGGGAGGGCACCCUGGUCUGUGCCUUGUGGGUGGAGGCGGGGCAGGGCUGUGUGGCACCGCCAGGGAGCGGGCCCACCUGAGUCACUUUAUUGGGUUCAGUCAACACUUUCUUGCUCCCUGUUUUCUCUUCUGUGGGAUGAUCUCAGAUGCAGGGGCUGGUUUUGGGGUUUUCCUGCUUGUGCCAAGGGCUGGACACUGCUGGGGGGCUGGAAAGCCCCUCCCUUCCUGUCCUUCUGUGGCCUCCAUCCCCUCAUGGGUGCUGCCAUCCUUCCUGGAGAGAGGGAGGUGAAAGCUGGUGUGAGCCCAGUGGGUUCCCGCCCACUCACCCAGGAGCUGGCUGGGCCAGGACCGGGAGAGGGAGCACUGCUGCCCUCCUGGCCCUGCUCCUUCCGCAGUUAGGGGUGGACCGAGCCUCGCUUUCCCCACUGUUCUGGAGGGAAGGGGAAGGAGGGGGUCUUCAGGCUGGAGCCAGGCUGGGGGUGCUGGGUGGAGAGAUGAGAUUUAGGGGGUGCCUCAUGGGGUGGGCAGGCCUGGGGUGAAAUGAGAAAGGCCCAGAACGUGCAGGUCUGCGGAGGGGAAGUGUCCUGAGUGAAGGAGGGGACCCCCAUCCUGGGGGAUGCUGGGAGUGAGUGAGUGAGAUGGCUGAGUGAGGGUUAUGGGGAGCCUGAGGUUUUAUGGGCCUGUGUAUCCCCUUCUCCCGGCCCCAGCCUGCCUCCCUCCUGCCCGCCUGGCCCACAGGUCUCCCUCUGGUCCCUGUCCCUCUGGUGGUUGGGGAUGGAGCGGCAGCAAGGGGUGUAAUGGGGCUGGGUUCUGUCUUCUACAGGCCACCCCGAGGUCCUCAGUGGUUGCCUGGGGAGCCGGACGGGGCUCCUGAGGGGUACAGGUUGGGUGGGCCCUCCCUGAGGGUCUGGGGUCAGGCUUUGGCCUCUGCUGCCUCUCAGUCACCAAGUCACCUCCCUCUGAAAAUCCAGUCCCUUCUUUGGAUGUCCUUGUGAGUCACUCUGGGCCUGGCUGUCGUCCCUCCUCAGCUUCUUGUUCCUGGGACAAGGGUCAAGCCAGGAUGGGCCCAGGCCUGGGAUCCCCCACCCCAGGACCCCCAGGCCCCCUCCCCUGCUGCUUUGCGGGGGGCAGGGCAGAAAUGGACUCCUUUUGGGUCCCCGAGGUGGGGUCCCCUCCCAGCCCUGCAUCCUCCGUGCCCUAGACCUGCUCCCCAGAGGAGGGGCCUUGACCCACAGGACGUGUGGUGGCGCCUGGCACUCAGGGACCCCCAGCUGCCGCAGCCCUGGUCUCUGGCGCAUCUCUUCCCUCUUGUCCCGAAGAUCUGCGCCUCUAGUGCCUUUUGAGGGGUUCCCAUCAUCCCUCCCUGAUAUUGUAUUGAAAAUAUUAUGCACACUGUUCAUGCUUCUACUAAUCAAUAAACGCUUUAUUUAAA